AGUUUCUGGCGCGAACUUCCGCCGUUCCGAAGUUGCACGGUGAAUUGGCGCUAUGUCUGGGGACAGCAGCGGCCGCGGGCCAGAGGGCCGGGGCCGGGGCCGCGACCCGCAUCGGGAUCGCACCCGCUCCCGCUCCCGCUCGCGGUCCCCUUUGUCGCCCAGGUCCCGCCGCGGCUCUGCGCGGGAGCGCAGAGAGGCCCCAGAGCGCCCGAGCCUGGAGGACACAGAGCCGUCGGAUUCCGGGGACGAGAUGAUGGACCCGGCCAGCUUGGAGGCGGAGGCCGACCAAGGCCUGUGCCGCCAGAUCCGCCAUCAGUACCGGGCGCUCAUCAACUCCGUCCAACAAAACCGUGAGGACAUACUGAAUGCCGGUGACAAAUUAACAGAGGUCCUUGAAGAGGCUAACACUCUGUUUAAUGAAGUGUCCCGAGCAAGAGAAGCAGUCCUGGAUGCCCACUUUCUUGUUUUGGCUUCAGAUUUGGGCAAAGAGAAAGCAAAGCAGCUGCGCUCAGACCUGAGCUCCUUUGACAUGUUAAGAUAUGUUGAAACUCUACUCACACAUAUGGGUGUAAAUCCGCUAGAAGCUGAAGAACUCAUCCGUGAUGAAGAUAGUCCUGAUUUUGAAUUCAUAGUCUAUGACUCCUGGAAGAUAACAGGCAGAACAGCAGAAAACACCUUUAAUAAAACCCAUACAUUCCACUUUCUGUUGGGUUCAAUAUACGGAGAGUGCCCUGUGCCAAAGCCACGAGUUGAUCGUCCAAGAAAAGUUCCUGUGAUACAAGAGGAGAGGGCAAUGCCUGCCCAGUUAAGAAGAAUGGAAGAAUCUCAUCAAGAAGCAACAGAGAAAGAAGUAGAAAGAAUCUUGGGAUUGUUGCAGACAUAUUUUCGAGAAGAUCCUGAUACCCCAAUGUCCUUCUUUGACUUUGUGGUUGAUCCUCAUUCUUUCCCCCGUACAGUGGAAAACAUCUUUCAUGUUUCCUUCAUUAUACGGGAUGGUUUUGCAAGAAUAAGACUUGACCAAGACCGACUGCCAGUAAUAGAUACUGAAAACAUGGCCAGCGUCUAAAAUUUUGAUGGAUUCAUCUAUAUCAUUGAUUCAACAUCUGCUGUAAAUAUUAACAAAGAAAUGAUAUAAUUUCCCUCAGAUCUUAAUUUAGAAAGUUGGUGAUUGCAGUCAUUUUUGUAGUAUCCCUCUUUCUAAUCACGUUUUGUCAGAUGCCGGCACCUUCUUUUCUCUUUGAGGUUCUAUGAAUCUUUCAUUCUUACCUGAAUAAUUUCACACUCUCCAUUACUCAUGUCCUCCUAAGGUCUCCUGUGGAGAGUGAAUAUUUCCAUCGCACUUACUUGCUACUUUCAAUGUUCUCAAUGUCCUAUUGGACUCACUAGGGCUUAGCUCUGUGGUUGACACAUAGAUAUGCAGAUUUUCAAAUGUCUGGAAUGUGUUACUCUACUACAUGUUUUUUGAAAUGGAAACAGAUGGAAUGACUGGCUACUGUAAUAAUACUACAGCAGCUCCAUAAUGCAUGAAAUCCUAAAAAGUAUGUAAUAUUAUAAGUAUCUUUUCAAUACAGGUUUCAUUGCUAUUAUUCAUCAGUUUCCGUUUAGAUUACCUGUUCCGAUUUAAUAACCUUUGAUAAAUUUGAAAAAUUUGUCUUUCAAA